AUGCCUCGCUUUGCAAGCCCUCUUUUAAGAAAUGUCAUUAUCAGAAGUCAAUUUGAUGGCAUCAAGAGGAAGCAAUGCCUCCAAUAUCUGAAAACCCUGAGAACACUGCAAUAUGAUGGAUUUAAGACCGUAUAUUUUGGGGAAACCAAUAUCCCAGAAAGUCUCGUAACUGGGGAAGAUAUUAGUGAUGGAUAUUUCAUACAAACCCCAACUUGGUGUAUUGUGCAUGCUGCGGGUAGUCAAGGAUGGGUGCCUUGGAAAUAUCGGGUGUUCCUAAGAGACGAGCUGUGUAUCAAACAAGAAGACAGCCUCUUCUCUGAGUUCUGUGAUGUGGUGAGGAAGGCCUAUGGAAAGUGUGUCAUCGUGGUCAAAGAGAGAAGGCAGCAGGAAGAGCAGAGGCCAAAGGAAGACAGAGAGGCUGAGGGCCAGUUCUAUAUCCCUACAGUCAUUAGCUUAGCAAGCAUUAUGUGUUGCCCAGAGGUGGCCAAGUCCUGUGGCCAUGAACUACUCUCUCUGCCUUCCCCUUGUAAUUAUCUGAACCCUUUAGACUCAGCCUGGUCUUCUCUGAAAUGGUUUAUCAUCAAUAACAGAAACGAGUUUUGUUUGCAGUCCAUUGACAGUGGCUAUUCUUACCAAUGUAUACUUUUCAGCAAUUUAAUUAGCAAAGGAAUUGAAAGGAUAAACGCAAGCAAGUGGAGAACAUUAACUAGCAAAGUACGGAGAUGGGAAAACUACUAUCUUGGGAAAUUUUCUUAAGGGUGGUUCCUCCAACAAGCAGUGAGGCUGCUACAUGUCUGGUCUUUACCGUCAACUCUGUUGAGAUGAAUUCCACACCACUGCAGCCAAAGAUACUUCAACAGCGACCUCACAUGGGGUGCUGCGAGAACUGGGUUGCUCCUAAGGAUGUUGGCAAAGCGCUUUGAGUUUACUAGAAGUUUCAUUAAAAUUUGUUGGUAAGUUA